AUUCGCCGCCCGGCCCCUGCUCCGUGGCUGGUUUUCUCCGCGGGCGCCUCGGGCGGAACCUGGAGAUAAUGGGCAGCACCUGGGGGAGCCCUGGCUGGGUGCGGCUCGCUCUUUGCCUGACGGGCUUAGUGCUCUCGCUCUACGCGCUGCACGUGAAGGCGGCGCGCGCCCGGGACCGGGAUUACCGCGCGCUCUGCGACGUGGGCACCGCCAUCAGCUGUUCGCGCGUCUUCUCCUCCAGGUGGGGCAGGGGUUUCGGGCUGGUGGAGCAUGUGCUGGGACAGGACAGCAUCCUCAAUCAAUCCAACAGCAUAUUCGGUUGCAUCUUCUACACACUACAGCUAUUGUUAGAGAUGGUGUCUCGCCAUGUUGCCCAGGCUGGUCUCAAGCAAUCUGUCUGCCUCAGCCUCCCAAAGUGCUGGGGGGAUUACAGGCGUUGCCUGCGGACACGCUGGGCCUCUGUCCUGAUGCUGCUGAGCUCCCUGGUGUCUCUCGCUGGUUCUGUCUACCUGGCCUGGAUCCUGUUCUUCGUGCUCUAUGAUUUCUGCAUUGUUUGUAUCACCACCUAUGCUAUCAACGUGAGCCUGAUGUGGCUCAGUUUCCGGAAGGUCCAAGAACCCCAGGGCAAGGCUAAGAGGCACUGAGCCCUCAACCCAAGCCAGGCUGACCUCAUCUGCUUUGCUUUGGCAUGUGAGCCUUGCCUAAGGGGGCAUAUCUGGGUCCCUAGAAGGCCCUAGAUGUGGGGCUUCUAGAUUACCCCCUCCUCCUGCCAUACCCGCACAUGACAAUGGACCAAAUGUGCCACACGCUCGCUCUUUUUUACACCCAGUGCCUCUGACUCUGUCCCCAUGGGCUGGUCUCCAAAGCUCUUUCCAUUGCCCAGGGAGGGAAGGUUCUGAGCAAUAAAGUUUCUUAGAUCAAUCA